ACUGAAUGGAGAGAGCGAGCGCCGGCCAGCUCACCCGGCCGCCCCGUGCCCCAGCCGCAGCCGCCGCGCUCCCCAGCCCAGCCCCAAGCCGGACCUCCCCGGGCGCCACGCCCCAUUGCGCUCGCCCCAGGUCCCCAACCCGGCCCGCGGGCCAGCGGGGCCAGGGGGCGCUCCGCACCUGGGCACUCCCAGCGAUGCGCAGCGGGGCAGCGCCGGCCCCGCCGAUGGAGCUGCUGUUGCUGCCGCCGCCGCCGCCCGGAGCGCCCCGCUCCGCCCGCGCCCCGUGCGCCUGAGCACCGAGCUCGCCCCUCCUCCGCGCUAACUCCGCCGCCCGCUCCCCAGGCCGCCCGCGCUCCCCGCGCGCCUCCUCGGGCUCCACGCGUCUUGCCCCGCAGAGGCAGCCUCCUCCAGGAGCGGGGCCCUGCACACCAUGGCCCCCGGGUGGGCAGGGGUCGGCGCCGCCGUGCGCGCCCGCCUGGCGCUGGCCUUGGCGCUGGCGAGCGUCCUGAGUGGGCCUCCAGCCGUCGCCUGCCCCACCAAGUGUACCUGCUCCGCUGCCAGCGUGGACUGCCACGGGCUGGGCCUCCGCGCGGUUCCUCGGGGCAUCCCCCGCAACGCUGAGCGCCUUGACCUGGACAGAAAUAAUAUCACCAGGAUCACCAAGAUGGACUUCGCUGGGCUCAAGAACCUCCGAGUCUUGCAUCUGGAAGACAACCAGGUCAGCGUCAUCGAGAGAGGCGCCUUCCAGGACCUGAAGCAGCUAGAGCGACUGCGCCUGAACAAGAAUAAGCUGCAAGUCCUUCCAGAAUUGCUUUUCCAGAGCACGCCGAAGCUCACCAGACUAGAUUUGAGUGAAAACCAGAUCCAGGGGAUCCCGAGGAAGGCGUUCCGCGGCAUCACCGAUGUGAAGAACCUGCAACUGGACAACAACCACAUCAGCUGCAUUGAAGAUGGAGCCUUCCGAGCGCUGCGCGAUUUGGAGAUCCUUACCCUCAACAACAACAACAUCAGUCGCAUCCUGGUCACCAGCUUCAACCACAUGCCGAAGAUCCGAACUCUGCGCCUCCACUCCAACCACCUGUACUGCGACUGCCACCUGGCCUGGCUCUCGGAUUGGCUGCGACAGCGACGGACAGUUGGCCAGUUCACACUCUGCAUGGCUCCUGUGCAUUUGAGGGGCUUCAACGUGGCGGAUGUGCAGAAGAAGGAGUACGUGUGCCCAGCCCCCCACUCGGAGCCCCCAUCCUGCAAUGCCAACUCCAUCUCCUGCCCUUCGCCCUGCACGUGCAGCAAUAACAUCGUGGACUGUCGAGGAAAGGGCUUGAUGGAGAUUCCUGCCAACUUGCCGGAGGGCAUCGUCGAAAUACGCCUAGAACAGAACUCCAUCAAAGCCAUCCCUGCAGGAGCCUUCACCCAGUACAAGAAACUGAAGCGAAUAGACAUCAGCAAGAAUCAGAUAUCGGAUAUUGCUCCAGAUGCCUUCCAGGGCCUGAAAUCACUCACAUCGCUGGUCCUGUAUGGGAACAAGAUCACCGAGAUUGUCAAGGGACUGUUUGAUGGGCUGGUGUCCCUACAGCUGCUCCUCCUCAAUGCCAACAAGAUCAACUGCCUGCGGGUGAACACGUUUCAGGACCUGCAGAACCUCAACUUGCUCUCCCUGUAUGACAACAAGCUGCAGACCAUCAGCAAGGGGCUCUUCGCCCCUCUGCAGUCCAUCCAGACACUCCACUUAGCCCAAAACCCAUUUGUGUGCGACUGCCACUUGAAGUGGCUGGCCGACUACCUCCAGGACAACCCCAUCGAGACAAGCGGGGCCCGCUGCAGCAGCCCGCGCCGACUCGCCAACAAGCGCAUCAGCCAGAUCAAGAGCAAGAAGUUCCGCUGCUCAGGCUCCGAGGAUUACCGCAGCAGGUUCAGCAGCGAGUGCUUCAUGGACCUCGUGUGCCCCGAGAAGUGUCGCUGUGAGGGCACGAUUGUGGACUGCUCCAACCAGAAGCUGGUCCGCAUCCCAAGCCACCUCCCUGAAUAUGUCACCGACCUGCGACUGAAUGACAAUGAGGUAUCUGUUCUGGAGGCCACUGGCAUCUUCAAGAAGUUGCCCAACCUGCGGAAAAUAAAUCUGAGUAACAAUAAGAUCAAGGAGGUGCGAGAGGGAGCUUUCGAUGGAGCAGCCAGCGUGCAGGAGCUGAUGCUGACAGGGAACCAGCUGGAGACCGUGCACGGGCGCGUGUUCCGUGGCCUCAGUGGCCUCAAAACCUUGAUGCUGAGGAGUAACUUGAUCGGCUGUGUGAGUAAUGACACCUUUGCCGGCCUGAGUUCGGUGAGACUGCUGUCCCUCUAUGACAAUCGGAUCACCACCAUCACCCCUGGGGCCUUCACCACGCUUGUCUCCCUGUCCACCAUAAACCUCCUGUCCAACCCCUUCAACUGCAACUGCCACCUGGCCUGGCUCGGCAAGUGGUUGAGGAAGAGGCGGAUCGUCAGUGGGAACCCUAGGUGCCAGAAGCCAUUUUUCCUCAAGGAGAUUCCCAUCCAGGAUGUGGCCAUCCAGGACUUCACCUGUGAUGGCAACGAGGAGAGUAGCUGCCAGCUGAGCCCGCGCUGCCCGGAGCAGUGCACCUGUAUGGAGACAGUGGUGCGAUGCAGCAACAAGGGGCUCCGCGCCCUCCCCAGAGGCAUGCCCAAGGAUGUGACCGAGCUGUACCUGGAAGGAAACCACCUAACAGCCGUGCCCAGAGAGCUGUCCGCCCUCCGACACCUGACGCUUAUUGACCUGAGCAACAACAGCAUCAGCAUGCUGACCAAUUACACCUUCAGUAACAUGUCUCACCUCUCCACUCUGAUCCUGAGCUACAACCGGCUGAGGUGCAUCCCCGUCCACGCCUUCAACGGGCUGCGGUCCCUGCGAGUGCUAACCCUCCAUGGCAAUGACAUUUCCAGCGUUCCUGAAGGCUCCUUCAACGACCUCACAUCUCUUUCCCAUCUGGCGCUGGGAACCAACCCACUCCACUGUGACUGCAGUCUUCGGUGGCUGUCGGAGUGGGUGAAGGCGGGGUACAAGGAGCCUGGCAUCGCCCGCUGCAGUAGCCCUGAGCCCAUGGCUGACAGGCUCCUGCUCACCACCCCAACCCACCGCUUCCAGUGCAAAGUACUCUGGUUUUGCUGCCCAGGGCCAGUGGACAUCAACAUUGUGGCCAAAUGCAAUGCCUGCCUCUCCAGCCCGUGCAAGAAUAACGGGACAUGCACCCAGGACCCUGUGGAGCUGUACCGCUGUGCCUGCCCCUACAGCUACAAGGGCAAGGACUGCACUGUGCCCAUCAACACCUGCAUCCAGAACCCCUGUCAGCAUGGAGGCACCUGCCACCUGAGUGACAGCCACAAGGAUGGGUUCAGCUGCUCCUGCCCUCUGGGCUUUGAGGGGCAGCGGUGUGAGAUCAACCCAGAUGACUGUGAGGACAACGACUGCGAAAACAAUGCCACCUGCGUGGACGGGAUCAACAACUACGUGUGUAUCUGUCCGCCUAACUACACAGGUGAGCUAUGCGACGAGGUGAUUGACCACUGUGUGCCUGAGCUGAACCUCUGUCAGCAUGAGGCCAAGUGCAUCCCCCUGGACAAAGGAUUCAGCUGCGAGUGUGUCCCUGGCUACAGCGGGAAGCUCUGUGAGACAGACAAUGAUGACUGUGUGGCCCACAAGUGCCGCCACGGGGCCCAGUGCGUGGACACAAUCAAUGGCUACACAUGCACCUGCCCCCAGGGCUUCAGUGGACCCUUCUGUGAACACCCCCCACCCAUGGUCCUACUGCAGACCAGCCCAUGCGACCAGUACGAGUGCCAGAACGGGGCCCAGUGCAUCGUGGUGCAGCAGGAGCCCACCUGCCGCUGCCCACCAGGCUUCGCCGGCCCCAGAUGCGAGAAGCUCAUCACUGUCAACUUCGUGGGCAAAGACUCCUACGUGGAACUGGCCUCCGCCAAGGUCCGACCCCAGGCCAACAUCUCCCUGCAGGUGGCCACUGACAAGGACAACGGCAUCCUUCUCUACAAAGGAGACAAUGACCCCCUGGCACUGGAGCUGUACCAGGGCCACGUGCGGCUGGUCUAUGACAGCCUGAGUUCCCCUCCAACCACAGUGUACAGUGUGGAGACAGUGAAUGAUGGGCAGUUUCACAGUGUGGAGCUGGUGACGCUAAACCAGACCCUGAACCUAGUAGUGGACAAAGGAACUCCAAAGAGCCUGGGGAAGCUCCAGAAGCAGCCAGCAGUGGGCAUCAACAGCCCCCUCUACCUUGGAGGCAUCCCCACCUCCACCGGCCUCUCUGCCUUGCGCCAGGGCACGGACCGGCCUCUAGGCGGCUUCCACGGAUGCAUCCAUGAGGUGCGCAUCAACAACGAGCUGCAGGACUUCAAGGCCCUCCCACCACAGUCCCUGGGGGUGUCACCAGGCUGCAAGUCCUGCACCGUGUGCAAGCACGGCCUGUGCCGCUCCGUGGAGAAGGACAGCGUGGUGUGCGAGUGCCGCCCAGGCUGGACCGGCCCACUCUGCGAUCAGGAGGCCCGGGACCCCUGCCUCGGCCACAGAUGCCACCAUGGAAAAUGUGUGGCAACUGGGACCUCAUACAUGUGCAAGUGUGCCGAGGGCUAUGGAGGGGACUUGUGUGACAACAAGAAUGACUCUGCCAAUGCCUGCUCAGCCUUCAAGUGUCACCAUGGGCAGUGCCACAUCUCAGACCAAGGGGAGCCCUACUGCCUGUGCCAGCCCGGCUUUAGCGGCGAGCACUGCCAACAAGAGAAUCCGUGCCUGGGACAAGUAGUCCGAGAGGUGAUCCGCCGCCAGAAAGGUUAUGCAUCAUGUGCCACAGCCUCCAAGGUGCCCAUCAUGGAAUGUCGUGGGGGCUGUGGGCCCCAGUGCUGCCAGCCCACCCGCAGCAAGCGGCGGAAAUACGUCUUCCAGUGCACGGACGGCUCCUCGUUUGUAGAAGAGGUGGAGAGACACUUAGAGUGCGGCUGCCUCGCGUGUUCCUAAGCCCCUGCCCGCCUGCCUGCCACCUCUCGGACUCCAGCUUGAUGGAGUUGGGACAGCCAUGUGGGACCCCCUGGUGAUUCAGCAUGAAGGAAAUGAAGCUGGAGAGGAAGGUAAAGAAGAAGAGAAUAUUAAGUAUAUUGUAAAAUAAACAAAAAAUAGAACUUAUUUUUAUUAUGGAAAGUGACUAUUUUCAUCUUUUAUUAUAUAAAUAUAUUACACCAUCUGCGUAUAUGUACCAUAUAGUGAGUUAUUUUUACCAAGUUUUGUGUUGUGUAUUUGUUGUGUUUUUAAAAAUAGCUGUUUAAAAAUUUAAGAAAAAAAUAGACUAAUAAAAAUGCUUUAAAACAAAAGGAUAAGAAUAAAGAAUGAUAGCCUGUCUGAGGAAGGAGGAAGAUGUUUUCAUGUUUAUGAAACGGUAUUAUGUCGGCAGUAGACCAAGAGCUGCUCAUUGAGAUCAGAAAAAGGAAUAAGAGGAAGAGAGAGAAGGAAAAGACCUUUGUUUCUUGUUUUUUAACUCCCUUUUAUUUUUCCUCCCCUAAAAUUACCCAGCUUUUCGGAGUCCUGGAUGUCAGUGCCCAAAAUGCCCAGUUCUUCCAGGAAAAGCUGCUGAGCCCUGGCCUUCUCAGUCUCACUGCCACUCAAAAAUAUUGCUGUCCCUGUCUGUCCCAGACCCCCCUUCAGGGUAUCUGAACCCACUGGGGGACCCCUCUUCUCCUUCCUGGGUGGCCCUGGCUUCCGUAUCUGAACCCACUGGGGGACCCCUCUUCUCCUUCCUGGCUGGCCCUGGCUUCCAAUCGAGGACUGACUAUUGAAGUCUGCUACAGGUGUCAUUUGGAACUGUCUUACCAAAUUUUAAAACAGCUGCUAUUUUUCCUGCUCCUCCCCAGGAGAGGGGUCUUCCUAGAGGAGGCGAGGGAAGAGAAUAUCAUGGUGUCUCCUCAGGACCCAUGCACUGGCCCUCUCUCCUCCUUCCAGGUAAUUUUUCAUUGGAAUGUAUCCCAGUAGAGAAGGUAGUCAGCCCUUCUUGGAAGCGGAAGGCUGGGAGCCAAGUCAAGUCUGCCCACAGCGCUAGAUGUCCAACUCUGGAAGGUUCUUGGAGGCUCUUGUUGUAAGACAGGCCUCUGCCACCUGAUCCUCCAGGUCACCAGCAUGACGAUAGAGACUCCUUGCCCAUCUGUGACACUUUCCAAUGCAUAUCCAAACUUUACCUUAUUUUAUCUAUGCAACCCCUGCCUCCCUGGGAAGGAUAAGGGAGUAGAGCUGGGUUCACUAAGAAGGAAGUUUAGGCCCUCACAGGCUCUGGAACUUGCCUUAAGCCACACACCAGAUAAGUGGAGGAGCCAGACCAGAAGUCCAGACCCAAAGCUUGAGAUUCUUCCUCUAGAAUGGGUGAGCACAGGUGAUUCAGGCGGCUUAAAUCCAUCAGAGCAGCCCUGCCGGAAAAGGAAAUAAUAUGAUGUUUUUUCCUGCUCUUGUUCUGCCUUGCUCACUCCUUCUCCCUCCGCAGUAUCUGGAAAGAUUCUGGAGACCAGGGCUUAUGCAUCUAGGGAAAGUGACCAAGGGCAGCCUAUCCAGCCUCUGCCUCCAUUCCUGAAGGGGACUUCCCUGCCCCUGUUUCUUUCCAUGUCUCUCCCUCCCUCACUCCCAUUUGCCCCCUUCCACCCCAUCAGGUUAGCCACAUAUCUUCCAGGGCUCAGCUGUUCACACCAACUCCCUGGCUCUUAUCAUCCAUCCCUCCUUCCCCCAGGAGCUUCCACUGUAGGAGUUUCAGGGAGAAGAGUUUGGAAUUCAUUGGACCUUUCAGCCCUCAGGUUCCCUAGAGGAGCCUAGUUGAUCUGUGAGUACCAAUGGUGGGCCAAAGACGCAGGGAAUAAUGAAGGGAGAAAGAAAAGAAAGGAAGAUGGAGGAAAACGAGGCAACUGGAAGAAGGAAGGAAGGAAAGAAGGAAGGGAUGGAGGGGAUGAAGAGAAGGGAGAGAGGGAUAUAGCUGAGGAAUUUAUCUAAAAAUGUGCAUGUAAAUCUCCAUUAUGUUCCAGGUACUGUGCCUUAUGAUGGCUUUGUUUUUUGUUGUCAUUAGAGACAAGGUCUUGCUUUGUCACCCAGGCUGGAGUAGAGUGGUUCGAUCAUAGCUCACCGCAGCCUCAACCUCCUAGGCUCAAGCCAUCUUCCUGCCUCAGUCUCCCAAAAUGCUGGGAUUACAGGUGUGAGCCACUAUGCUCAGCCUGUUUCAAACAUUAUUAUAAUAGCAGAUUUAUUUAGUACUUUAUUAUACAUCAGAUACCACUCUAAUUGUGAAAUAGAUAUAUAUUCAUUUAAUUAUUGAAACAACCAUGUAGUUAAAACACUAUUAACUCAUUUUACAGUUGAGUAGACUGAGACACAGAGAAGUUAAAGAACUUGCCCAAGAGUAAAUGUCUAAUAAACCGUAGAGCCAGGAUCUGGGCCCAGGCUGUCUGACUCCAGAACUUGCUCACUCAACCACUAAACCAUCCUGCUUCUCAUGGGAAAGAAACACAUCCUGCCUUUGAGGAUCCUACAGCCUGUGACAAAAACAGUCAUAAAAAUGGACAAUUGCCUUAUUACACAAGGAGCUCUUAAGUGGCAAUACAAGCAAUGGAAGUGGCUGUCCAGAGGAGGGAACUUCUAGUCCUAGGUCUUUAAGGAUGAAUAGGAGUUUGCCAGAGUGAGAAAGGGAAUUGAACUUUCCUGGGAGUGGCCUUUUAAAAAGCAAUGAGAUAUGGCCAGGCCUGGCUUGUUUGGGGAAGAGUCAAAAUCUAGGGUGGCAAGAGUAUGGGAAGCACACUGAGGAGCAGAGAGAAAUGGGGUAGGUAGGAAGGUAGGGUUUUGACCACAAAGAGCUGUGCAUGCUAAACUGGGCCACAGGUGCCAGCAGGGUUGUUUGAGGAAGGGAAGAGCAAGACAAGCUCUGGUUUAGGAAGAGAGCUGUGGCAGCAUAAAGGCCUGAAAGAGGAGACAGAGCUGUCACCCAAAAUGGACUUGAGAGCUCCCUGUGGUUUACUCUGUGGCUAGAAAACACUGCCGGCCAGAUGGAUCACAAAUGUCUAUGGUAGCUUAGAAGCUCUGCUCUUGAAGAGGAUCCUGGGAUCUGCCCAACACCCUUCCCAACCUCCAUUUCCCCAUCCCCACCUCCAUUGCCCCAUCCCCCCUCUCCCCCUAGGCAGGUGGAUCUGAGCCUUAUCCCACCACCAAUGCCCCUGCUAGCCUCUCCCCACCCAGCCCAGAGCCUACUCAGCCUGCCAUCUCAAGAGCCCCACCGAGGGUCACUGGCUUCCUGGGAGGAGUCACCAGGCUGCCAGCUUUCCCUCUGCCUCCCCAAGGAACCUGAGACCUCCCUCUGCUCAUCACCCUGGGCCCAAUCCUGAAUCCAGCCCCCAUCAACCAAGACAGCAAAAGGGCCAGGUCUGUCCCUUAUAAUUUUGAGCCUUCUCCCUCAAGUUUGGAAGCCCUGACUUUAAGAAAUGCCAAAUGCAAGGACCAUUAAGAAAAUUCUCCCCGAAAUGAGGCUCCUCUAACAAAUGAUGAUUAAAACGCUCUCUCCUUGAGCAGUCACAUUCUAGAAACAGGACAUUCCAUGAGGCAGGAAGAGUUCAGUUAAUUUGCUCCUGAAAAAGUGUGGUUCAGUGUUUGUGUGGCAAUGUACGUGGGCAGAAGAGGCCGCUCAAGCUGUGUCCCCCCUGAGCAGGAUUCAGGAAAGGGAAAAGAAGUUCUCUUCAACUCAGCCAAGGGGCCGUACGAUGGCCGAUGAGAUUAUGUAUUUAAAAGUUCUUUGUAAAGUGUAAACUAAAAACCUUAAAUGUAAGAUGCUGUUGUUAUUAUUACUGUUGUUGUUGCUGUUAUGGACAUGCCAAAAGGCCCUUGUUAGAAGACAGUUUUGCCUUUUCAAUCUCAUAGCAAGGAACUCAAGUCUGAUGCUUCAAAAAGAUGAGAAGAAGGGCAAGAAGAGGGAUAACUCCCAAGCUCAGAGGGAAAAAAAAGGUGGGGGAAAAGAGCCCCAGGGUGACCUUCAGGAAAGGCCAGGACCAGGAUGAUCUAACCUUUCCCUUCACCAGAAACAAAGCUAUUGCCAGACUGAACCCUAAAGUCAAGCAGUCACCCACUGCCUUUGCUGGGAGCAGAAGCCCAUAGCAACAAGUGACCUGCCCCUCAGACUCAAGAUCCCAGAUACCAGAGCUGGAGGAGUCAUAGGGCAUUACUGGUAGGCAGGAAAACUGAGGGUCGAACAAAUGGAAGAAUGCGGUGAUCAUAGACCAAAGACACACAGAUAAUUAACCCCAUGUGUCCACCCAGGCCAAAGUUCUUCCUGCUACCCCACAGUGGAUGUCCAGGCAGAUGGUCCCCACAUGAUGGGGAAGCAGAGGGCAUAGUGUGGUUUUGUGGGACUUGUUCAUGUUUUGUAGUGUGGGCUCAACAGUGCCAAAGGAAACACUAGGGAAAAGUUGGUGAAACAUGCCAGCUAGCAGGACCAGUAAAGGCAUAAUCAGGCAUUUGGCAAAGCUUGCUUUUCUAAUUCAAUGAUAGGUUCUAAUAGGAAAUUUUUGAAGAUUUUUUAAAACAAUGUUAUAGUGGCACUUCCCCAGUAUGGAAUAAAUAACAUGCAUUCUUUUUUCAAUAUACUGUCAUAUUCAGAUGUCAUUAAAAUAAAUGGAUGAGUCACAGAGGAGCUAUCAGAUGCUCUCAUGACUACCAUAACUCA